GCUUCCUGUUGGGGCAUGAGUCCGGCGCGUGUCGGGUUUUGAGCUGCCGCGGUCCCGGGACUGAGGUGGGUGGCGGGGUCCGCCCGUCUUGGGCGUCACUCCUCGCCAAACCUUUAGCUCAAGUCUUAAUGAAUGUCCUCUCUGUGGUUCUAAUCCGAGCUCCAGCCCCACGGGUUCCUGCAGGGGCGGGACCACCUGGCCCAACCUCUGCCUUGGUCCAACGCCCCCGGUUUCCUCCAGGGCCUUGGUCCAACGCCCCUCGGAGGUUUCAGCCCAUUUCACAGACCGGGCCGCAGGGCCCCGGCGUAGGCCUCGGGACCGGAGAGGCCCUCAAGGGGAGUUGAACAGGGCUGCGGCCGCCGCGCCCCGGGCGGCGACGUCACCGCCCUUGCUGGUGAUUGGCCGCCUCGCGCCGCGCGCCCUUCAAACCUUUUCUCCCCGUGGCUGUCGGCGCCCGCUGGGCGGGAGGCCUUUCCGGAGGCGGCCGCUCUGCGCCUCGGCGUUUCCUCCAAGGCUGCCCACCAGAAGGACCUGCCCGAGAGGGUAGAGGGCAUAGGGUCAAGAUCAAGCUCCUUGGGAGCAGACAGCUGUCCUCACUGGCAGAGGAGGAGCGCUCAGUAAAUGCUCGCUGGACGAAUAAAUGGCUAGAUAAGAUAAGGCAGCUCCAGCCCCUGGAAGGCCAGAGACUUGCCAGUGUCCCACUAGCGGGCUCUUCGCAAGAAUCCCCCCGGGCCCGCCGCAGCCAGGCGGCGGCCGGCAGAGGGCGCUGCUCGGGCAUGGCGGAGGAGCGGCCGGGGGCCUGGUUCGGCUUCGGUUUCUGCGGCUUCGGGCAGGAGCUGGGCUCCGGACGCGGGCGCCAGGUGCACAGCCCCAGUCCGCUGCGGGCGGGCGUCGACAUCUGCCGCGUGAGCGCGAGCUGGAGCUACACCGCUUUCGUGACCCGUGGAGGCCGCUUGGAGCUGUCGGGCUCAGCCAGCGGCGCGGCGGGCCGCUGCAAGGACGCGUGGGCCUCGGAGGGGCUCCUCGCGGUGCUGCGCGCCGGGCCGGGGCCGGAGGCGUUACUGCAGGUCUGGGCGGCCGAAUCGGCGCUGCGUGGGGAGCCAUUGUGGGCCCAGAAUGUGGUGCCCGAGGCCGAAGGGGAAGACGAUCCGGCCGGUGAGGCCCAGGCUGGGAGGCUACCCCUGCUGCCCUGCGCCCGUGCCUACGUGAGCCCGCGGGCGCCCUUCUACCGGCCUCUGGCUCCGGAGCUGCGGGCACGCCAGCUGGAGCUGGGCGCCGAGCACGCGUUGCUGCUGGACGCUGCUGGCCAGGUGUUCUCCUGGGGCGGGGGCAGGCAUGGACAGCUGGGCCAUGGGACCCUGGAGGCAGAGCUGGAGCCACGGCUGUUGGAGGCGUUGCAGGGCCUAGUCAUGGCUGAGGUGGCCGCGGGGGGCUGGCAUUCUGUGUGUGUGAGUGAGACUGGGGAUAUUUAUAUCUGGGGCUGGAAUGAAUCAGGGCAGCUGGCCCUGCCCACCAGGAACCUGGCAGAGGAUGGAGAGACUGUCGCAAGGGAAGCCACAGAACUGAAUGAAGAUGGUUCUCAGGUGAAGAGAACGGGUGGGGCUGAGGAUGGAGCCCCUGCCCCCUUCAUAGCUGUCCAGCCCUUCCCGGCAUUACUGGAUCUCCCCAUGGGCUCAGAUGCAGUCAAGGCCAGCUGUGGAUCCCGGCACACAGCUGUGGUGACACGAACAGGGGAGCUCUACACCUGGGGCUGGGGUAAAUAUGGACAGCUGGGCCACGAGGACACCACCAGCUUGGAUCGGCCUCGCCGUGUGGAAUACUUUGUAGAUAAGCAACUCCAAGUAAAGGCUGUCACCUGUGGGCCGUGGAACACCUACGUGUAUGCUGUGGAGAAAGGGAAGAGCUGACAUGUGUACGUAUAUGUAUAUGCAACACCUGUGAGACCCCCAUUCAGGUCAAGGAAAACCAUUGCCUGCACCCCAAGGGCCCCAUAUUUGCCCCUCCCCAUCACAGUCCUGCCCUUCACCCUCAAGCACGGUCCUAAACUUGUCUGCACUUUAGAAACACCUGGAGAGCAUUGAAAACUCUGCUGCCUAAGGUCAGCAUCAAUCAAAACAAUGAAAUCAAUGAAACAAUGAAACCAGAGCUUCUAGGUGUGUGGCCUGGAUAGUGGUAGAUUCAAAGCUCCACCCACCUCAUCCCAGGUACAUUUGAUGUGCAGCUGAGAUUGGGGCACAUUCCAGGUCAUCGUCUUCUGUCAGUCAUUUCCCUGCUUUCGUUUGAAUUUUACCAUUCUUGUAUGCAGCCUUAUACGACAUAGUUGUGUUUGCUUUUGAGUGUUAGAUAAAUGGAAUCCUGUGUAUGUGCUUUUGUGUCGUUUUUGUCACUCAGCAUUGUAUAAUCCAUCCUUGUUGGGUCCUGGAGUUCAUUUUUAAUGCUAUAUGGUGUUCUGUUGUAUGAAUAAUACCUCAAGUGAUACAGCCUUGUUGAUGGUCAUUUUUAUUGUUUCUGAUUUUGGUCAUUCCACAUAAUUCUUUGUGCAGUCUUCUGCACAUGUGCACAAGUUCCUUUGCAGAACAUUGAGUUGAAUUGCUAAGUCAGGAGAUACCUUUAAUUUUACUAGAUAACUGUUGCCCCCAGCAGGGUGGGGUCUACUGUGGCUAAAAUGUCAGGUAGAUGCACACUGGUUUUAAUUGGCAUUUCCCUGGAUACUGAUGAGGUUGAGUAGCUUUUCAUUUGUUUUGGAUGGCUGGGCAUGGUGGCUCACACCUGUAGUCCCAGCACUUUGGGAGGCUAAGCAGGGAGAUUGCUUGAGGCGAAGAGUUCAUAUGUUUAUUGGCCACUUGGAGUUUUUCUGUUGUCAAGUGCCUGUUCAAGUUUUCUGGCCUUUUAAAAUGUUCUGUAUUUUCCUUAGUGAUUUUUCUUUUGGAUAUUUCAGAUACAAGUCUUUUGAGAGUUAGUAUUCAGAGUAUCUUCUGCUACAAUGUAGUUUGUUUCAGUCUCUCUUGGUAUUACCAAUUUUAAUACUUAGGUGAUGCUUACUCCAUGCCAGGUAAGGCUCAAAGUGCUUUACAAGUAUCAACUUAUUUUGAUAAAAUAAGCUUAUCAGUAGUUUUCUUUAUAGUUAAAUUCUAUUUGUGCAUGUGUGUGUCUGUGGUUUAGCAAAUGUUUCCCACCCAUGGGGUCUUUUUUAUUGUGGUAAAAUAUACUGAACAUAAAAUUUAUGUUCAAUAAAAAACAAAAAUUGUUUUUAACCAUUUUAA